CGGGUAGUGGAGCCGCAAGCCACCGGCAUCUUGCUUUUUCUUCCCCCUCCUCCUGUGUGCCCCGCGCCGCUCCCUCUUUCCCUUUUAUUCCCGGCCCCACCCGCCAAAAUGAACAGCUCGGACGAAGAGAAGCAGCUGCAGCUCAUUACCAGUCUGAAGGAGCAAGCAAUAGGCGAAUAUGAAGACCUUAGAGCAGAGAACCAGAAAACAAAGGAGAAGUGUGACAAAAUUAGGCAAGAACGAGAUGAAGCCGUUAAAAAACUGGAAGAAUUUCAGAAAAUUUCUCACAUGGUCAUAGAGGAAGUUAAUUUCAUGCAGAACCAUCUUGAAAUAGAGAAGACUUGUCGAGAAAGUGCUGAAGCUUUGGCAACAAAGCUAAAUAAAGAAAAUAAAACGUUGAAAAGAAUCAGCAUGUUGUACAUGGCCAAGCUGGGACCAGAUGUAAUAACUGAAGAGAUAAACAUUGAUGAUGAAGAUUCGACUACAGACACAGACGGUGCCGCCGAGACUUGUGUCUCAGUACAGUGUCAGAAGCAAAUUAAAGAACUUCGAGAUCAAAUUGUAUCUGUUCAGGAGGAAAAGAAGAUUUUAGCCAUUGAGCUGGAAAAUCUCAAGAGCAAACUCGUAGAAGUAAUUGAAGAAGUAAAUAAAGUUAAACAAGAAAAGACUGUUUUAAAUUCAGAAGUUCUUGAACAGAGAAAAGUCUUAGAAAAAUGCAAUAGAGUGUCCAUGUUAGCUGUAGAAGAGUAUGAGGAGAUGCAAGUAAACCUGGAGCUGGAGAAGGACCUUCGAAAGAAAGCAGAGUCAUUUGCACAAGAGAUGUUCAUUGAGCAAAACAAGCUAAAGAGACAAAGCCACCUUCUGCUGCAGAGCUCCAUCCCUGAUCAGCAGCUUUUGAAAGCUUUAGACGAAAAUGCAAAACUCACCCAGCAACUUGAAGAAGAGAGAAUUCAGCAUCAACAAAAGGUCAAAGAAUUAGAAGAGCAACUAGAAAAUGAAACACUCCACAAAGAAAUACACAACCUCAAACAGCAACUGGAGCUUCUAGAGGAAGAUAAAAAGGAAUUGGAAUUGAAAUAUCAGAAUUCUGAAGAGAAAGCCAGAAAUUUAAAGCACUCUGUUGAUGAACUCCAGAAACGAGUGAACCAGUCUGAGAAUUCAGUACCUCCACCACCUCCUCCUCCACCACCACUUCCCCCUCCACCUCCCAAUCCUAUCCGAUCCCUCAUGUCCAUGAUCCGGAAACGAUCCCACCCCAGUGGCAGUGGUGCUAAGAAAGAAAAGGCAACUCAACCAGAAACAACUGAAGAAGUCACAGAUCUAAAGAGGCAAGCAGUUGAAGAGAUGAUGGAUAGAAUUAAAAAGGGAGUUCAUCUUAGACCCGUUAAUCAGACAGCCAGACCGAAGACAAAGCCAGAAUCUUCGAAAGGCUGCGAAAGUGCAGUGGAUGAACUAAAAGGAAUACUGGGGACACUUAACAAAUCCACUAGUUCAAGAAGCUUAAAAUCCCUUGACCCUGAAAACAGUGAAACUGAGUUAGAAAGGAUUUUGCGUCGCAGAAAGGUGACAGCAGAAGCAGAUAGCAGUAGUCCAACUGGGAUAUUAGCCACCUCAGAGUCCAAAUCCAUGCCAGUGUUGGGUUCUGUAUCCAGUGUAACAAAAACAGCCUUGAACAAGAAAACUCUGGAGGCAGAAUUCAACAGCCCGUCCCCCCCAACACCUGAGCCAGGUGAAGGGCCCCGUAAAUUGGAAGGAUGCACAAGUUCCAAGGUUACGUUUCAGCCUCCCAGUAGCAUUGGAUGCAGGAAAAAAUACAUUGACGGUGAAAAACAAGCCGAACCAGUUGUAGUUUUAGAUCCUGUUUCUACACAUGAACCCCAAACCAAAGACCAGGUUGCUGAAAAAGAUCCAACUCAACACAAGGAGGAUGAAGGCGAAAUUCAACCAGAAAACAAAGAAGACAGCAUUGAAAACGUGAGAGAGACAGACAGCUCCAACUGCUGAUCCAUAAACCAGAAGCCUGACAUGUUUGGAAGUCCUUUUCAAUAAGCACAUGAUUAGUGUUGUUAUAUUGGCAAGGGCUGUAGACAUUCUGCUCUGGUCACUGUAUUCAGAAUACAGGUUCUUUUCUGGUGUCACUUUUGUAAGUAGCAACUAUAAACAUAAGUAAGCUGUUUAGCAAAACACACAUUCCUAGUAGGUUUUGGUUUUUUGAUCUUUAUAAAGAUGAGGUUUUUUUCCUAGUUACUGUAUUAAGUAUGACUUCUUUUAGAAGGUUACAAAAAAAUUCAGAUGUUGAUACCUUUUUAGGAAAUGUGCAUACCACUCAUCAAAUGGAAUGCUGAAAGUUUGAGGUGCUUGUAUAUAAUCGGAUAAACAAAACUGAUCAACCCAAUGUGAUUUUAAAAGCCCCCAAAGAAGCUUCUGUUUUGGGUCUGAUCCUCUUGAUGGAGAAACUGCAGCAGCAUGGAAAUUGUUGGGUACUGUGGCAUACAAGUUAUUUUCUACAGUAGACUGAGAUAAACUGAAAACUCAGGAGCUGGCAUCAAACUCGUAGUCCCAUAGUCAGUGUUAAUUACACACAUUGUUAACUAUUGGAUGAAAAAUACAUGCUAUUGAUUGUGUCCAAAGCCUCCCGAGGACCUCCGUGGGGAUGCUCUGGUAGCCUGAAUACAGAACUGAGGUGAAAGUCCAAACCUUGAAUUUUACAGUAGUAAGUUGGUAAACCAUGUGCUCUGUGCUAUGAGUUAAUUAUGUUUUCCCAAAUACUAAUGUGGCACAAGUACCAUAUUUUAUCAGAGUUCUUAUGUACAGUAUGGUGAAGAUAAGUGACAAGCACACAUUUUUCUUGCUUCACUGCUGUUCUAUAUUACACAGGUUUGUUGUUGUUUUUUUUAAAAAAGAAAUUAAGCAGUAGUUAGUCUCUAAAAAUACAAUGUUUCAGGCUACCACAGUGAAUAAAUAGAAAUGUAAUCAGGGAUUAAAAAAAAAACUUAUGCAGCUUUUCAAAGUUGAUUGUUUCAAAAUUGGUGUUUAUUUAAAAUAAGUGGUAAUGUACUUGAAUGCACUUUUUAUGACAAUGAUUCAGUAAUGGUAAUUUUACUAUUAAAGAAAGUGAAAGGUUUAGUUUUGUUAGCAUGGCUCAGCAUGUAGCUGUCAGGUGUUUUUCACCUAAGGGCAAAAGAAAAUGAUAGUAAUAAUUGCAGUAGUUGUAUUGUAUUGUAUUUUUGCACGUGUGGUAAGCAUAGGCUUGAAGAGGUGGGUAGGCAGGUACAUGUACUUCCUAAAUUUGGAGAUAAUUAUCUUUCUGUAAGUUCGUUAUGCUUGACUGUUUCCAUGUUCUCCCAAUAAUGAUUUUAUAGUUACUUAUCACUUUACUCAUGGAGAAUUAAAACGUAAUGUUUUUCAACUGUAUCUUUCUUUAACUGGAUAAUACUGCUAUAUGAUAUGCUUACUACAGACUGCAUUAAUUCACGAAACGAAUUCUGUUAUGCUGUAAUUUGAACUCUCCUCACCACAACUUAUUAAAAAGGCACCAAUAGUUUCCCAUUAAGGGUCAGUUGUGGUUAUUAUUAACGUUUCUGGUUUAGUUCCCCAAGCUUGACAUUCUUUAAUAGAAAAUUGUAUAUGAUUUGACAACUUUAGUAAUUUUUAAUAGUCCCUAAGAUGGUUUAUUGAGUUUUCUUUCAUGUUUCUUUGUGCUGUCUUCCUUCUUGCAUCUGUGAUCUGUCUGCCAGCAUGCAACUCACACACAUUUAGGAAUAUAAAAAUAUGUACACUGUCUUUCCAUAUUUCAUCACACCAUCACAGAAUAAUAUGGUUAUCAAAAUACCCUCCUUUCUAGAGUAAGAAGUUGCCCUUUGGGUGAAAUGUGUUAGCUGGACUAGGGAACAAUUAGUAACAGGUAUUUUGAAAGUAUUCCUGCCUUUUUUAAGCUGCUUACUUUCUCUCACUGUGAUUACAAAGCAUUUUAAAUUAAUUUGACAUGAAGGUAUUUGAUGGAAGAUAUUCACUCACCUUUUUCUGCCUACAGUUUUUCCCUUUUCACUUUGGUUUUGAGGGGGUUUUGCCCCUGGCUGGGGUGACACUGUCAACCAAAGCAAGGGAUCCCAAAUAGGAAGACAUAGGAGAACCGUGCUUAUAUCUGCAAGGUAUGUUCAUAGCUAUUGCACACACAAAACUUACAUACGUCCUGCUUACACAAUUUUAAGUUGGAAAAGACUGCAUCUUUAUGUUUUUGAUUUCUCUAAAAGGUUAUUUAUGCUUCCUUCUGUUUGGGAAAGAUAAAUUAAGUCUUGUGCGCUAUAGAGGAUUUUUUUUCUUUAAGAAAAACGAAUGUUGAUGCAUUUUAUAGCCCGAGUGAGGAACAGAGAUAGAGGUACUUUGUGCCAUUGCUAUUAAAGAAAAAGAAAAUGUCUCUUUUUUUUUCUGGAAGAAUAAGAUUUUAAUUAAAGCACUUGCACCCUUUUGUAUGUGAGCUGGUCUCAAACAAAGUCCUCACCCACAGCAGUUUCAGCAGCUGAACAGUCCCAUGGAAGUUCUGACUGGCAGGCAUCAACAGGGCUAUUAGCACCCAGCAUAGUUUGCCCUGAGUACGGAGGAUGGAUGCUUUGGCUCUAACUACUCACCAAUAAUUGCUCCUUCCUUACCUUCUUUGUUAAUGGUAAACUGCUGGAAAUGGAGUAGUACAGGUAACAAUUAUUUUUAAUUGUCUUUCCAGACCAGUUUUUGGUUGUGUGUUCAGUAAAUGAUAGUCUGUAUCACAGCCUUCAAGUCUGGAUUAUUUUUCUAAAUGCAUACUCUACCUGUUCAGUUACACUCGUUGUGGAACAACAUUAGCUUAUAUACCAGUAAGUUGUCGAGAAUGGAUAACCAUCUGUCAUUAUCACUGACCUUCAAAGACUCAUCAAGCAGUCCCUGCAUAAGGAUUGGAGUGGUUUGAAGUUUCUCUUCCAAGCACUAACAUGUCCCUAUCCCACAGUCAUUUUAAUUUGGUAUGUGACUGUUUCUUUCAUUUCUUUCACAGAUAAUAUUAUAUAUACAGUUAUAUAAAUAUAUUUCAUAUUAAAUGUUAUAUAACACAAGAGAGAGAAAGUAUAAGUAGAAAGAGUGCCUAGCACCCUAAGAAAUUUAAAUUAAAAUGCUAAUUAUCCAUUGGUGAGUGCAGUCUCGAGGAUAGGUGAGUAAACUGCUCUGUGUUGAAGUCACACUGCUGACCUGGUUAUUGUAAUAAAUCACCUCUUUGGUUAAUUUAAUUUAGUUAUUUUGUUAUUCAUUGUACAUUUUUGCUCUGGUUUUAGUAAUUUAAUUAUAAUUUAUAUCACUGUUCCAGGGCAUAGUCUCAUGAUGUGUGUGUGUGUGUGUGUGUGUGUGUGUGUAUUUUUCAAAGGGUAUGUGAACACCCAGUCAUGUUUGUUCUGCCUUUCAAAUGAAUUUUCCUUCCAGUUUCUCCUACCCGUUGCUUGUUGCUAAGCAUCAGGAGAGGCAGUAGCAGCCACAAACUGUGACACAGUUCUUCCAACUUAGAGUGAUACCAACCAAGUCUCCUGCAUGCUCUGAGAGAGUCUGCGCCUGAGCCAGUUUCAAAUCAUAGCUUUGAGAAUAAAGAGUUGGCUCUGUUAUGAGGAAAUUAAGGUCCCUUGUUAGUACUCUUUAAAAGGAGAGGUCCUCAGUGUGCUUAAUAAAAAUUAUAGAAUUUGUCAGAAGUCUAAACUUAGCCAACUCCCCUACAGGUCAGUACAUAGCAAUUUAUAUAAUUUUUAGGAGAAGCAAAUGGUAACCAUUUUAACGAGACCCUAAAUCAUAUAAAGUGGUUGGAUAUUAUUAUAUCUAUAUGUUUGUGUCUGAAUAUAUUUAUUUCUGCUACUCCUCUGCUAUAAUCCCAACACUGGCUUACAAAAGAGCAAUUCAGGCAAUGGAUAUGUCACAUCAUUUUUUUUUUUUUUUUUUAUCACUUGCGGAUUGCUUUUUAAAUGCUGUGGUAUGAAUAACUGGGCAUUUAAUAACCUUGAGAAUAUUAAUUCAUUUACUGAUGUGCUUAUUCAUUUAUACUCAUUCUUACUCCAAAAAGGAUCUAAGAAGACUCGCAAAGAUAAAAAUAAUACAAGAAAAACUAAAAUUUAAAAAGGAGAGGGAAUUAGGAAAAAAGGAAUCAAGGGUAGGAAAGUGAGAUGAAAUUGGCUCUUACAAAAAAUGGUGAUGCUCUCACACUUCUACGUGAGGUUGGUUACAAAAAUGUGUCAGUGCUUUUCAGCACAGACAUGUAGAAUAAACACAGAAGAUGGACAUCUGUUCCCAGCACAGAGAGCUUCUAGGGUCAUUAGGUUUUUGUUCUCAGAGAUAUUCUGAUUGGUAAAGGAUGGGGUGUUUGACUGAGUGUGGAGUUGGCAACAAAAAUAUUGGCCUCUUUUACUGGAGCGUGUCCCUGAAAAAUGGACAGGAGAGCUAAUAGACAAACAAAAUCCACAUGGAAGUGUGGUGGCUGCAAAACGAAGUUCACAGAAUUUCAGGCAAAAACAUCAUAUAUGUAAUUUACCAAACAGUGGAAUUAGAAGAAUAAAAACCACAAGAGUUGGUGAAGUUGAAGAGGAAACUCCAUGUGGAGACACGGCGCCGUACUUCAGACCUCCCGGUCUACUAAUACUGAUGGUGUGGCUGGAACCUGGGGUGUGUACAGCCCUAUCCAGAGGAUGCUCCUGUUUCGGCUGAUUCCUCUACACCUUGUGUGGGGAAGGUGGGCACCAGCGGCUCCCUAGCCGCAGCAGCCUCAAGUGCCUCCGCAGCCUUUUCAGCUUCCUCAUUAAAGUAAAAAAAAGUGUGUUCUUCUUUGAAACCUAUUUAAAGUAACAAUAAAGUUUACUGUCUAAUCCAA